GCGUGCUUGAGAAGGUUCAAUGGCGUGGCAGGGACUAGCGGCCGAGUUCCUGCAGGUGCCGGCGGUGACGCGGGCUUACACCGCAGCCUGUGUCCUCACCACCGCCGCGGUGCAGCUGGAGCUCCUCAGCCCCUUUCAACUCUACUUCAACCCGCACCUUGUGUUCCGGAAGUUCCAGGUCUGGAGGCUCGUCACCAACUUCCUCUUCUUCGGGCCCCUGGGAUUCAGCUUCUUCUUCAACAUGCUCUUCGUGUUCCGCUACUGCCGCAUGCUGGAAGAGGGCUCCUUCCGCGGCCGCACGGCCGACUUCGUCUUCAUGUUUCUCUUCGGGGGCGUCCUUAUGACCCUGCUGGGACUCCUGGGCAGCCUGUUCUUCCUGGGCCAGGCCCUCAUGGCCAUGCUGGUGUACGUGUGGAGCCGCCGCAGCCCUCGGGUGAGGGUCAACUUCUUCGGCCUGCUCACUUUCCAGGCACCGUUCCUGCCUUGGGCGCUCAUGGGCUUCUCGCUGCUGCUGGGCAACUCCAUCCUCGUGGACCUGCUGGGGAUUGCGGUGGGCCAUAUCUACUACUUCCUGGAGGACGUCUUCCCCAACCAGCCUGGAGGCAAGAGGCUCCUGCAGACCCCUGGCUUCCUGUGAGUGUUGAGAGCCCUCCCUCCCUCUCCCCACCCUCAGAAGGAUCCCCACCGAUGGGGACCUGUGCUGGCCUGUGCUCAACACGGGCCCCUCCCCACAGAAAGCUGCUCCUGGAUGCCCCUGCAGAAGACCCCAAUUACCUGCCCCUCCCUGAGGAACAGCCAGGACCCCAUCUGCCACCCCCGCAGCAGUGACCCCCACCCAGGGCCAGGCCUAAGAGGCUUCUGGCAGCUUCCAUCCUACCCAUGACCCCUACUUGGGGCAGAAAAAACCCAUCCUAAAGGCUGGGCCCAUGCAAGGGCCCACCUGAAUAAACAGAAUGAGCUGCAGUCUCUUGGCCCACAGCACUGGCUUCCCCAUCUCACCUGGCCACAUCCUUCUAUGCCUGCCCCGUCCUCACUCAGUGUGGCCUCUCAGCCCAACUGCAGGUGGUAGGAUAGGGGUGCCCACAGAGGGCAAAGAAACUGCCCAUGGUUGCCUGGCAGAGCUUUGAGCUCACAGGUUGCCAGGCAGAGCUUUUGAGCUCACAGGUGACAGGCUCAGGGUUCUCAUCCUGGCCCCACCAGGGCCUUGGGCAAGUCCUGCCCACCAUAGGCCUCUGCUACCUGCCAGUCAGCGGGGAAGUUCACCAGAUUUCGGCUGCUGGGGCCAGGACAGGCGUCUCCUAGGUUGUGCCAAACCAGCCUACAGAUGUUCCUGCCAGUGGUGCCUUCAGGCUGAUGCCAAUCUAGCCUCUCCUGUCUCUCAUCAGCCACCCUGACAGGUGGGCGUAUGCCUCAUUUUUCAUCUGGUGAUGCCAAAGCCCCAUGGAUUCAGGUGCAGAAGAGGGCCAGGACUAGGUCUUCUGCCCUUUCUAUGACCUCAGAGCCUAAGUUUUCACCUUAGCAGAGUUCUGAGACUGGGUGAGGCAGGGACUUCUGGAAGGUUCUGUUCCUGCCCUUUUUAGCUGAGGACGUGUGUGAGCCUUAUCCGACCCCUGUGGCUCAUUUUUCUCUUCUGACCUGGCAGCUUUCCUUGUUGUUCUAAGCCUGUCCAUGUUGUGGUUUAUUUCUGGAUGCUCAGUGGCACGGGGCCUCCUCCAAAGACAGGUUGUCAUUUUCAUGGUAACAACACUGUUCUCUGUUGAGUCUGCCCUCCGUGUUGUAGCCAGACCUUGUGGAGAUGGCUUUGCGGCGGUGUGAGCUGGCGGUCAGGAGUGAGGGCCCAGCCUUCCCGGCACCUCCCAGCCAGGUGGCCCUGCCCGACCUGUGGGGUGAGGCAGCCAAGGUUCCUUCCAUCCCCCCAGUUGUGGAGACACAGGGCUGCCUCACCCUUUCAUUGCCGAGGUUCCUACCUCAUGGACAGAACAAACACCUCAGCAAUGAAACCUGUUCAUGUCUAAGAGCAGCUGGGCUGGGAAUCUUCCCCUUUGUUCAAGGCCUUCCAGUAAGGCCCAGCUGUCCCCUUGCUGUGCAUGGGGCUCUGGGGAGUUCCACUCUUUGAUGGAGGGCAGAGGCCCUGAGUGCAAACUCCCUGGGAAGAGUCCCAUGCUAACAUGUGCUCAAAGGAGCCCUCCUCUCACAUCUCAGCGACCAAGAACCCCAAUCCCUAAUCAGAGCUCUGCCUCUGCCCCACAUGGGGCCCUACCCCACUUCCAGGGAGCACAGCAGCCUCUGACCCUAGCCCUGCCCUGGCAGCAUGGGACCUGCCAACAGCUGAGGGUGGCAGCAGUCUGUGCUGGGAUCUGUGCCCGGAUCUGUGCCCAUUCUCUUCAGUAAGGCUGGAGCUGCGAGCCAGUUUGCUGCCCUCCCAGAUCCUGUGUCCAUUCUGAAGAAUGGGGACACCUCCCUAUUACAGAUGAGAACAGAGGGGACAUGAACUCCUUGGAGGCAGGGCUGGGAAGGGACCCUGGGCUGUGUCUCCUCCCUGUACCGUGUCAACUCCAAGAGCUGGCACCAGGCCGGGAGGGCUAUUCCCAUAUUCCUCACAGCUGGCUUGUAAGGCAGGAGCUGGCCCAGGCCACAGCACCUGCUGGGGUGGGAAAGGGCCCCAGCUGACCUGGCUAUGGGUGCCACUGGAGCUAGAACAGCCCUCCUGCACCCAGGCUGGCGACAGCCCAGCAGUGCCCACACAGGACUGGGCCCUCCGCAGGGGACUUCAGAGCAGCAAGGCCCCAGCUGGCAGUAGCCUGACCAUCUGGACACAGCAGAGCCAGGGCGGCCCAGGGACGGCAGGAGAGCUCGCGGCACCUUCCUGAGGCCAAGCAAGGGGAGCAGGGUUAGGGCUGUUCCUGAAAGGCAGAGAGCCUCUUGCCCUGAGCCUCACAGCUACUCUUCUCAGCUCUCUGGGUCUGGAAGGAGAACAGGCUGAGGGGAGCUGAGAGGAGCUGAGGUGCUACCCGGAGCCCCAUUCACCCCCACCUGCCCACUUGGGAAUCUGAGGCAGAGGAGGGUGAGGCCUGUGUGCCAACCUUGUUCACAUACCACCUUCGUCCCCCCAGGCCCCGGCCCCACUCCUGGCUCUCAUUAUUUUUAUGUUAAAACUUUGAAGAAAUUGAACAUGACCUGUUGAAGAAAUUGAA